ACUGUGUCCGGGUCAGCUGCUGCCGCCGACGCCGUACCGCUGCGGCCGGGGGAUUGGGCCGGGGUCUCCACCGCCGACCGAGGGGAGCGGGCUCCGCUCGGCCCUGCUUUUUGCGACCUGGCCGUCAGCCCCACGUCGCCGGCCUGGAGGGGCGAAGAGGACGAGGGGGCCAAGGCUUCCUCCGGGGACAUUGGCUCCCUGGAUUAUCAAGAGUUUGUAGUUGACAUUGAAUCCAGGCUGAGGAUGGAAGGUGUGGAACUUAAAGAAGAAUGGCAAGAUGAAGAUUUUCCGAUACCUUUACCAGAAGAUGAUAGUAUUGAAGCAGAUAUACUAGCUAUAACUGGACCAGAGGACCAGCCUGGCUCACUAGAAGUUAAUGGAAAUAAAGUGAGAAAGAAACUAAUGGCUCCAGACAUUAGCCUGACACUGGAUCCUAGUGAUGGCUCUGUAUUGUCAGAUGAUUUGGAUGAAAGUGGGGAGAUUGACUUAGAUGGCUUAGACACACCGUCAGAGAAUAGUAAUGAGUUUGAGUGGGAAGAUGAUCUUCCAAAACCCAAGACUACUGAAGUAAUUAGGAAAGGCUCAAUUACUGAAUACACAGCAGCAGAGGAAAAAGAAGAUGGACGACGCUGGCGUAUGUUCAGGAUUGGAGAACAGGACCACAGGGUUGAUAUGAAGGCAAUUGAACCCUAUAAAAAAGUUAUCAGCCAUGGGGGAUAUUAUGGGGAUGGAUUAAAUGCCAUUGUUGUGUUUGCUGUCUGUUUCAUGCCUGAAAGUAGUCAGCCUAACUAUAGAUACCUGAUGGACAAUCUUUUUAAAUAUGUUAUUGGCACUUUGGAGCUAUUAGUAGCAGAAAACUACAUGAUAGUUUAUUUAAAUGGUGCAACAACUCGAAGAAAAAUGCCCAGUCUGGGAUGGCUCAGGAAAUGUUAUCAGCAAAUUGAUAGAAGGUUACGGAAAAAUCUAAAAUCCCUAAUCAUUGUACAUCCUUCUUGGUUUAUCAGAACACUUCUGGCUGUUACAAGACCAUUUAUUAGCUCGAAAUUCAGCCAAAAAAUUAGAUACGUGUUUAAUUUGGCAGAACUAGCAGAACUUGUCCCCAUGGAAUACGUUGGCAUACCAGAAUGCAUAAAACAGUAUGAAGAAGAAAAGUUUAAAAAGAAACAAAAAAGAGUUGAUCAAGAACUUAAUGGAAAACAAGAUGAACCGAAAAAUGAACAGUAAGUUUGGCAUCUAGUCCAAACAAGACUGAAGAAUGUGCUGAUGGAGCAGUGCUGUUUCUGCAUUCAUAAUGCAUUUAUUGGCCCAUAUUUUUAUGUAACCUGUUACAAAAUAGACUUGACUUUUUCAUAAUGGACUUUUGUAUUAUACAAGGGACUGUUCACUGCUGUACUGGUUUGCAAAUUUCUUGAAUUUAGCUCUUUAAUAGCUAACUGUAUUAUUAUCGUUUUAUAUUUUAUAUUGCUAAAUAGAGAACCACACUUUAUAUAAAGUAGUUUUUGCAUUUGUUUAUUGAAUGAUGCAUCUUCUUCGGUGAAAUAUUUAUAUGCAUAAAUGGCAAAGGAAAGAAAUAAUAUAUAUUUUUAUGUCAUUGAGCAAUAUUUUUUAAUGUGUACCUGUCUUAUGGAAGAAAUAUGCAGGUAUAUAAGACCACGAUUUUCUAAAGUGCAUAUUAGAAUUUUUGUUUUUGUAAAUGGUUAAAUACAUUUCCUGGGUAACUUAGGAAAUUAAGUUUUUCAUAAGGCAACAGAUGGUUAAACUGAUUGUCAUGAAUACCCAAAGAUCAUGUAUAUAAUCGAAGUGUAUUAGUACCAUCCCAAGGUUUUUUUCUCAUUUAACAUAUUUGUUUCAUAAUUCAGCAAGUACAGAUGCAAGCGCAUUGCACACUUUUUCCUUUCUAAACUUAAAGACAAGUCAAAAAGCCAUUCUUAGAACUAGAGGAUUUAAGAGGGUAGGAAUUAGGGUUUGUAUAUAUGUAUAUAUGGGACAUUUUAUCUUCUGGCCCAAAGUCAGAACUUUAUAAAAAUCUUGAGUUUGUUCACUAAUGUGAAAUAAGCUAUGUGUCCAGGGUAUUGCUCCCCUGAGUGUAUAUGAGUGCUGAGUAGUAUUGCAGAGAAUGUGAUGAGUUAUUCACUGUCACAACUUUUUCUAUAGAAAACAGGGGCUGCUUUUUAAACUCUCACUAUGGGCACUUUACCAAAAUACUUCCAUAUCAAUUAUUUGAACUCGGUAGUUGUUUGACCUAGUUAGAUGUGGUGUUUAUUCAAGUUUGUAUGAAAUCAUGUUUGACAAUACUGUAAAUUAGGUUAAUUUUGUAAGUCUUAGCAUCAUCAUAUUGUGCUGUUUUGGAUAACACGUUUGUUACAAGCAUUUAAACUGUUUCAUUUGGUAGUACCUUUACAUUGAAAUAAAUUGUGUUUGUGCCUCCAAACAAAAAGUUUAAUUACCGACAAAAUUAUUUCUAAAACAACAGAUUGAUCUGAUAUUGUGUCAUAUACUUGAAAGGCUCAUACACAGCUGGUAAGCAUAAUACCUUCCAAAUUUGAAGGUCAUGGCUACUCUUCAACCCUUCCUGUAAGGUAUUUUACAAAACAGUGGCCUAGAGUAGCAAAAUUGAAGUGGAUGUGAGCUAACCUUUCAAGAUUUAGUCUAUCCUAGAUUGAACACACAUGUGGCUGUGACCAUUCUCAUGUACUUACAAACCUUCUGUUACAAAAGGGAACUUUCCUAUAUUUUUUGUCCUCCUCAGUCCUAAACUUGGCAUGCUAACUUAAAACCAGUUAUAGGAGAGAGAUGCUGGAGGAUUCCCAGGAUGAAACAUUCCUCAGCAGCCUCCUGACUUAACUCAGAUCCAGCAGCUCUUGGCAGAUCCUGAACUAAUGUCAUUACAGUGAAUUGAGCCAAAACGAUUAUUGCUUGCUCACAUUUUAGGAACACUUGUUGUUGAAGAAGCAAACUAACAAUAACAAGUUAGGCAUUCCUUCUGAAUUUACCAUAUAAGGAUUAUGUAUAAACAAUUAUAUUGAAUUUGUCAUUAGAUUCUAUAUUUGUAGACGAUUUAACGUAGUCUUUCAUCUGUACAUCUUUAUCUUGCUCAAAAUGGGCUGAGGUUUUUAAUAGGUGGUUUUCUACCACAUUAAGUACUUGGUUCUUCAGUUUAAAAAAUAUGAAGAAUAACUUCAACUCUUUUUUGCAUUAUUUUGAUUUUUGAUUUUGCAGUCAUUGCUCCUAACUGUAGAUACAUGUUGCAAAAGUGAUGUUUUUCUGAAUUUUUUUUAAAAGUAGAAGACUAUUCUGUUAAACAUUAAAAUUCAGAGACAACAGUGAUAACACCUGGGAUAUAAUGAAAAUGAGGUGCUGUGAAUCAGUAAACUAAAGGGAUACCUGCUUUAACCUGCACCUUAAUGGAAUCUGGUAUAGAGAUGUACCCACAAUAAAUGUUUUAUAAGAUUUAAGAUCAUAAUAGUAGGUUAGAGGAAGAGCAUUUAUUAAGUCUGUUGUUUCUAAUCUAUAGCUAAGUUAACAUUUCCCAUAUUAUUCCAUUUUAAUUUCCCAUUACUGACCAAGGUGAAAGUAUAUGUGAUUGUACUUUUAUCUUUCUGUUGGGAUCAUGGAUCUAAUUUAACUGGCUUAAUUUGAUGCUUCUGUCACUAGGCUCUAAGUGCCCCUUUUUUAGUCAGAAGUUUUUCAUGUGAAAUAAUUUGAUUCUGUGUUCUGCUUGAUCAUACUCCUAAGCAAGCACCAAGGGAAGACGUUCUAUUCACCCCACAAUUUAAGCUUAACAAUCUUUAACUCAGAGGGAGAUAUGAAGAAAUAUGAUUCUAAGUAGGGUCUAGCAGAGGCAUUGGAAAGUGAUAAAAGUAGGAAGUAAGAGAAAGCAAACCUUUAUAAAGAGAUAAAGACAUAGUUGUUACCUAAGAUGCCACUGUAUGUGUGCCCUCUCUUUUUUUUUUUUUUUUUUUGGAGACAGAGACUCACUCUGUCACCCAUUCUGGAGUGCAGUGGCGCAAUCCUGGCUCACUGCAACCUCUGCCUCCCGGGUUCAAGCAUUUCUCCUGCCUCAGCCUCCUGAGUAGCUGGGAUUACAGGCACACGCCACAAUGCCCGGCUAAUUUUUGUAUUUUUAGUAGAGACGGGGUUUCGCCAUGCUAGGCUGGUCUCGAACUCCUGACCUCAUGAUCUGCCUGUCUCAGCCUCCCAAAUGCUUGGAUUACAGGCUUGAGCCACCACGCCCGGCCAUGUGUGUCCUUUUAAGGGAAGUACCAUAUGUGACUGCUGAUGGUAACAUUUCUUGUAUGCAGCAGGAAAACCUGCAGGCUAUACGCAAGGUAUGUGAAUAAAGACUGUGGAUUGAAGGGGGAAAAGUUGAUAAUACAUACCCAUGAUAAGAAUUCAUAUUUUCUCUUUCUUUGUCUCUUCAUACAGAAGCAAGUUCGAGCAGAGAAGGUUAGCAGUUACAGCACUUAAAAGUUUAGGAUUGAGGGUUUUUGGUUGGUUUUUUUGUUUUUUCAUAUUUCACUGUUGCUGAACAUUGAUUUAGUCUUCCAAAAUGGACAUCACUAGUAAGUGCACUGAAUACUGAAAUAUGCUGAUUGGCAAGCAUAUAUCUGUAGCUAGAAUUUUUUUAACCGUAAUUCCAGAAUUUAAAAAGGUAAGAGAUCUGCUUUUUGAUAGAGGCCUUUUAAAAAGACUAUAUAACAUUUCUAUUUGGCUGUUUAUGUGAAUGCUCAGGGAAUUUGGACAUGUGUUUUAUACAGAAGUGGCUUUUUAUAUUUCUUCAAGUGAUAAAUUAGCAUUAGGACAUAUCAGAUAGAACAGGCCAGUUUCCUGAUGAGAUUGGUAGAGAUGUUACGGUAGGUUCAUCCUUCCUUUUUCCAUGUUAUAUGUGGAGAAGUGUUAAACUUGCUCAAGCAAAUGGGAGUAGGAGAUAGGCUGAAAAUAGAGAUUGCUACACCAUUCUAUUUUGUUUUCAUGCCUGUUUUUUCUCCAAUCCUAUAUGGACAUUUGAGAAAUGGACCACAAAUCUGAGAGGGAUAGAGUAAAAAGAGGCAUUAAUGUAUGUACUCACAAGUUAGACCUAUUUUGCUGUUAAAAUAGGUCUGGUCUUGUUAUAGGUCAUAGGAAUUGUGUAGUUUGAGUUGCUGCGAGAAAGAGUCAAGAACUUAGACUUGAAUGGGAAGGCCAACUGGUGAGGGAAGUGGGGUAUUAUCUACUCAAAUGUUCUAAGCUAAUACAAAAGAAUUACCUGGCAAGCAUCCCCCUCUGCCCUUCUUGAAAUUCUGAAUGAACUUAGAAUCAGAUCAAUGGUGAGACCCAGUUAUGUAACUUUCCUUUGAAGUUCUAAAGGAUAAUUGAAAAUAAAGUAGUCUGGCAUGUUUAACAGUAAGGAGUGACACUAAAAUUUGAAUAUAACAGUAUGUUGCAACUAUUUAUAAUAGACCUAUUUAUGUUUUGAGAACUAAGUAAAAUGCUAUGAAAAAUUCACAUAAAGCACGUAAGCACCAAAUGAAAAUCAUUUCGUGCUUUCAAAUUAAUGAUACUAGGCUUGUAGGAUGUCUUAGAAUCAUGUUUAACAAGAAGUUAAAAUAUUUGCAUUUUGAAAUUUUUAUGCAGUUUGGCUAAGGAGGAACUUGGAAAAUAACAUUCAUCAGCUUCUACACUGCACUUUUUGUAUGUGGACUUUGUAAAGUUUAAUGUCCGUUUAACAGUUGCUUGUUUAUUUGUGUAAACCUAGCUAGUAAAUAUUGAUGAUGUUCAGGGCCACUGACUUGCACAGCCCUUGGAGCACUAUUCACACAGAACACAAUUCAGAGUUUGUUAAGACAUUAACACACUUUGAUAUCUAUUCCAAAAAUACUUUUGUUACCACAGGUUCAUUGCUGUCAUUUAGACAAAAUUAAUGUACUGUGAUAUUUUCCUACUCUUAAGAUGAUGUUGCCCAGCCGAGUACUGUCAGAAAUUCAGUUCUGAUGUCUGUGUGUGCAAGAUAUUAAUGUGGUCCCUGUAAGAAAUACCAGAGUUGGUCAUGAUUUACUAAGGAGAUGUAAUAUUUUCUUUGACCUGUUAGGAAUAUAACUUGUGUCUUGAUUUGUUGCACAUCAUAUUUUUUGCAACAUUAAUGAAUUUAAAUAAAUUAAUUGGAACGUU